AUAUCCUAAUAGAUUGAGAUUCAAACUGAUGCAGCACAUUUUUUACGGGGACUACUCAGAUUGCUGUUAUGAAAUACAAGUCAGAUUUAUGAUCUUUUUCAUAUUGAACAUGAUAUGCUAUGCUAACGCUGCAUGUGACAGUUUAAUCAAAUCCAUUUGUUACCAGGAAGCUAAAAGGGGCCGCUGGGAUUUUAGGAUUACGGGCAGAGUUAGGGAAGCAUGUGGCUUUGUCAUUCGCCAUCAUUUUGCACACUGCGAGGGGCUCCGUGUGUGCGCCCUGUCUUGUCUGGCCGUCCUCAUCCCUUCCCCCACCCCCUGCCGCCACUCCGACCCGCUCCCAAAGUGGCUUCACAAUAGUCGGUCCUCGGCGGUGUAGGCUGCGCACCAGGUCCACACUUAAGCGAAAUCAAGGAGACCCCCUUCUACUUCUACCUUUGGGUUUGGUGCUCAAUGCGAAGCUGCUGCAACUCAGACACGCCUAAGUCAACUCAUGCAGAAAAAGGAGAAAAGUUUUGGUAUACAAAUGCUCUCAGUCCAGCCAGACACCAAGCCGAAAGGUUGUGCUGGCUGCAACCGAAAGAUCAAGGACCGGUAUCUUCUAAAGGCACUGGACAAAUACUGGCAUGAAGACUGCCUGAAGUGUGCCUGCUGUGACUGUCGCUUGGGAGAGCAUUUGAAGAGGUGUGGAUCUAUAUACAUACAUGCUGCACAUACAGAGAUUGGAAUCUGUGUAACCUUAGAAUGGCCAUUACCUUUUGUCAUCAUUGACUUUAGCCAACAAAUCACCAUAGCUUGGCUCUUUGGUGUAACGGGAAACUGCGCUGCCUGUAGUAAGCUCAUCCCUGCCUUUGAGAUGGUGAUGCGUGCCAAGGACAAUGUUUACCACCUGGACUGCUUUGCAUGUCAGCUUUGUAAUCAGAGAUUUUGUGUUGGAGACAAAUUUUUCCUAAAGAAUAACAUGAUCCUUUGCCAGACGGACUACGAGGAAGGUUUAAUGAAAGAAGGUUAUGCACCCCAGGUUCGCUGAUCUAUCAACAUCACCCCAUUAAGAAUACAAAGCACUACAUUCUUUUAUCUUUUUUGCUCCACAUGUACAUAAGAAUUGACACAGGAACCUACUGAAUAGCGUAGAUAUAGGAAGGCAGGAUGGUUAUAUGGAAUAAAAGGCGGACUGCAUCUGUAUGUAGUGAAAUUGCCCCAGUUCAGAGUUGAAUGUUUAUUAUUAAAGAAAAAAGUAAUGUACAUAUGGCUGGAUUUUUUUGCUUGCUAUUCGUUUUUGUGUCACUUGGCAUGAGAUGUUUAUUUUGGACUAUUGUAUAUAAUGUAUUGUAAUAUUUGAAGCACAAAUGUAAUACAGUUUUAUUGUGUUACCAUUUGUGUUCCAUUUGCUUCUUUGUAUUGUUGCAUUUAGUACAAUCAGUGUUUAAACUUACUGUAUAUUUAUGCUUUCUGUAUUUACCAGCUAUUUUAAAUGAGCUGUAACUUUCUAGUAAAGAAUUGAAAAGCAAAUCUCACUAAUGAUACACAGAUAGAUAAAGCAAGUCUAUCAACAUUAAAAAUACUAAAAAAUAAAGACACACACAGAGCAUUUUAGUGACAUCCACUACUUAUUGCCGCUAUGAGUUAGAGUCUAUCAGUGUUCUUGUUAUAACCCCCUAUUUUCAGGGGGUUAAAAAUCAGCUUUAAAAAAAUACAUAAAAAUUUCAUCUUAAAGCACUUUCAUUUUAUACCAACGUGAAAAGUGCCAUUUUUAGAAUAACUUUAAAGCUUAACAGGUUUCCUUUUAAUAUCCUUUUUUUGUGUGCUCUUUACUUACACAAUGGCUUUGUUUUGCUUUUUCAGCCACACCCCUUAUGUGAACUAGUGCCUUUGGGUAUCACGUAAAAUUUUUUCCAAAGGGUUACUUUAAAAAUCUGUUACCACAAUUAUGAGAUGAUUUUUAAGUGAUAAAUUAAACUUCUUCUUGUAUAAAUUCUGCCCAGAUCUCUCCACAAGAGCUGAGGGUUUCAUAACUUUAUGGCUUAAUAAAUGUAUGACACUGAAAAGAUUUGAGUGUGAAUCUACUGAAAUCACUAUAAUGCACAUUGAAGCUAUGAUGGUAUUUGAGUAGUGAGGUUACUUUUGAUCGGAGCAACAUAAUGCUCAUAGAAUCUUCUAGAAGAAGAGAAACAAAGGGAUUGAUAAAAUGCUGAGAACUAGUGAUUAUAUAUUUUUCUGUAUUUACCUGACAUUUAUUUUAAUGUUCAAAAAGUAAACACUUUAAGUUUGAUGUGUUUUACUCUCUCAUUGUUUUAAGUAAUUGCCAACUCAGAAUACAUCAUUCUUAGGCUGAAAUUUGUCUUUCCAUUUUUUAAGGUGAAAUAGUACUACCUUACGUGAUAGCAUACAAAGAAGAAAGCUCUAGAAAGAGAAAUUAUGGAGAAUGAUUAUUUAAAUUACAAUUAAGGAAAUGAGAAUAUGAUCCCCUCUUCCGAGUUGCCCACAAACUUGCUUCUUUGCUUUUGCUCCCUGUAAUAGAACUACUUUUCAACAAAUCUAAUUUUGCACGGCACCGUUAACCAUAUUUUCACUACAGCAAACUUAGUGCUAUGGGUUUUCUUUUUCUUUGUUUUUUUCUUGAUCACUUGUAUAGGAAACAAUAUUUUCCAGUGUUAUUUGCAUAUAUAUUUUGUCCUUCCAAUAUAUGCAUUACAGAUGAAAAUUAAAUGUUAUACCUGAAUUCUUGGGUUGGGGCCAAAAUAUUAAGCUGAAAAUAAUGCUGGUGUGGAUUUGUUUUAAAACAAAGCUUUAUUAUGAACAUGCAUGUGAAUCUGGAUAUUGCCUCUUAUUUUUAAGAAAAUGGUUCUGUGAAAAGUGAAUGAUAUGUAUUUUUCCAAAUGCUUCAUGGUUAGGAGUCUUCAAGUUCCAUGUUCCCCAGAUUUGAGAUAUACUAAAGAAAGAAAUUCAAAAGUAGCUAUUUGGGGCCCACAAAAAUAACUAUUAUUUUAGCCUUAGAGCCUUACACUUGUUUCAUGAAGAGAAAGGACUUGCAUAACCAAAAUAAACAAAGCAAGACAAAUUAAAAAUAUGUGGGGGAGAGAUCAGUGAAAAGUGGUUUUCUUAAUGCAGCCCUGCUGGUCCCCAUUAACAAUUGCUUGAAAUUCACAUGGAUGUAAAAUUAUAAUUGUCAGGAUCUUAUUCAGAUGAUCUUUUAAGGUUUAACUGGUUUUGCUUUUGUUUAUCUAUAUGUCAAAAUACUUGUAAAUUGGGAACAAACUUCUCUCAGCUUCUUGAAGUUGUUCAACUAUCCUUGCCACUGGAAGACCAAACAAGGUUUUCACUGCUUUUUCUUUUACAUAAUAUGCUGAGAAUUAUUUCUUAUGCUUUUUACUACAAACAAAAUUACUCACCUGGAUUAAAGAUUAAGGCCUUAAUCUGUUUAGAUUAUCUUUAAUCUCCAUGAAAUCGUGAAAUAAGACAAGAAUAGUGUUUCAGCUGUAGGCCAUUUUACAGCUAAUUGCCCAUAAAUUGUAGCAUUUAUUGACCUGAAGUACUAAGCUAAUUGUCUUGACUACUCAAAGCCCCUGAAUUGUUGUCAACUUUCCCCUUUGUGUUGUGUAGCCCUAACGUCAUUUAGCUUGUUGUCUGAUGCCUCCAGUAGGACACCUCCGAUGGAGCUUUGAUUUCUGAGCAGCGAAAGCUCCCUUCCUAAGAUGCAUCUCGCAUAGGCUGCCUAUGAUGAAGGACCGUGCACCUCCACUCCAACAGAGUGCUGAGUUUAAAAGUUGACCUGUGUUUGUAAUUUCACUUUCAUCUUGCUUAAUAAAUAUCUGCUGGAUUCUUUCAUUCACUUUUUUACAUUUGGAUUUAUGUUUUUAAUAAAAGGGGUGUUACACUA